AUUCGGAGACAGUCGUGCCAGCCGGUGGGCCACCCAGCGAAGCGGCCGCCUUUGCAAGGUUGCUGGACAGAUGGAACUGGAAGGGCAGCCGUCUGCCGCCCACGAACACCUUCUCAAGCACUUUGAGUGACCACGGCUUGCAAGCUGGUGGCUGGCCCCCCGAGUCCCGGGCUCUGAGGCACGGCCGUCGACUUAAGCGUUGCAUCCUGUUACCUGGAGACCCUCUGAGCUCUCACCUGCUACUUCUGCCGCUGCUUCUGCACAGAAUCUGCUCUCUGGCCAGCGAUGAAGCCCCGUGCUAUAUACUCUGAGAAUGAGAUACAGAAAUCAGAGAAACGCGGCCGCUGCCUUUGCAGAAGACGCAGAUCAAAAUCUCCACGGGGCGUCUGCGGAGGACAGCAUGCAAAUCUCGCUGGGCAAACGGUCUGCUUCGUUGGGUGAUGCAAUACAGGAAAAUCAACACACAGCGGCAGAGCUCAGAGCAUUUCCUACGCGUUUUUGUGCUUAGCUAGGAGGAUUCUUGCCUUGUGAUCUGAGGCCGACGCCAGCAGGUCCUCUAUCCCCUGACGCCUGCCAGCUGCCAGUUCACUGGGGCUGGUGGGUCACUUUGAAGUCAGUAGAACACAGAGUUCGUUCAGAGGCAGGUGUUAUCACAGAAACAGGGGUCACUGGGUCUACAAAGAUGGGGAACUUUGAGGGUGCGAGGGUUGGAAGCUGAGCUCCACUAAACCCAAAGCUGGACUCUCCUAAUCCCAAAGCUGGACUCUCCUAAUCCCAAAGCUGGACUCUCCUAAUCCCAAAGCUGGACUCUCCUAAACCCAAAGCUGGGCUCCUUAAACCCAAAGCUGGGAUCCCUUAAGCCCAAAGCUGGGAUCCCUUAAACCCAAAGCUUGAAGAAAAUGUGACUACCUGGCCGGGCACGGUGGCUCACGCCUGUAAUCCCAGCACUUUGGGAGGUCGAGGCAGGUGGAUCACCUGAGGUCGGGAGUUCAAGACCAGCCCGGCUAACAUAGUGAAAUCCCAUCUCUGCUAAAAACACAAAACUUAGCCAGGCGUGGUGGCAGGUGCCUGUCAGCUACUCUGGAGGCUGAGGCAGGAGAAUGGCUUGAACCCGGGAGGCGGAGGUUGCAGGGAGCCGACGUUGUGCCAUUGCACUCCAGCCUGGACCACAGAGCAAGACUCAGCCUCAAGAAAAAAAAAAAAUGUAUUGCGUGCUGCAGAGUGACCUAAAGGUCAGAGGGUGCAGGGACCGUCUUCUUGUGACCAGCAUUCAAUGAGAGUUCCGGUACUUCAUCUGUUGGUAUCUCUAGAUCUUAGUCACCCUGAGACCUGUCGGCCGGCAUGUCUCGGCGGUAUUAAUUUGCAAUUCCCUGAUGAGCUACGACAUGGAGUGAUUUUUCACAAUUCAGUGCCCAGAAAUUUCUGGACAGCCACCUCUGCAGGCCAGACACCGCCAAGAACAACCGUUGUGCUGAUUUUCUAAAAUUUCCAUCCUGCCCGCUGAGCCCCGGCGGGGCCCAAACCGCAAGCCUGUGCCUCCUGUGUCAGGGCAGCUGGCAUCAGUUAGAGAGCCCGGGCGAGGACCCCUCCAGGAUGCAGGUCCCGAACAGCACCGGCCCGGACAACGCGACGCUGCAGAUGCUGCGGAACCCGGCGAUCGCGGUGGCCCUGCCCGUGGUGUACUCGCUGGUGGCGGCGGUCAGCAUCCCGGGCAACCUCUUCUCUCUGUGGGUGCUGUGCCGGCGCAUGGGGCCCAGAUCCCCGUCGGUCAUCUUCAUGAUCAACCUGAGCGUCACGGACCUGAUGCUGGCCAGCGUGUUGCCUUUCCAAAUCUACUACCAUUGCAACCGCCACCACUGGGUAUUCGGGGUGCUGCUUUGCAACGUGGUGACCGUGGCCUUUUACGCAAACAUGUAUUCCAGCAUCCUCACCAUGACCUGUAUCAGCGUGGAGCGCUUCCUGGGGGUCCUGUACCCGCUCAGCUCCAAGCGCUGGCGCCGCCGUCGUUACGCGGUGGCCGCGUGUGCAGGGACCUGGCUGCUGCUCCUGACCGCCCUGUCCCCGCUGGCGCGCACCGAUCUCACCUACCCGGUGCACGCCCUGGGCAUCAUCACCUGCUUCGACGUCCUCAAGUGGACGAUGCUCCCCAGCGUGGCCAUGUGGGCCGUGUUCCUCUUCACCAUCUUCAUCCUGCUGUUCCUCAUCCCGUUCGUGAUCACCGUGGCUUGUUACACGGCCACCAUCCUCAAGCUGUUGCGCACGGAGGAGGCGCACGGCCGGGAGCAGCGGAGGCGCGCGGUGGGCCUGGCCGCGGUGGUCUUGCUGGCCUUUGUCACCUGCUUCGCCCCCAACAACUUCGUGCUCCUGGCGCACAUCGUGAGCCGCCUGUUCUACGGCAAGAGCUACUACCACGUGUACAAGCUCACGCUGUGUCUCAGCUGCCUCAACAACUGUCUGGACCCGUUUGUUUAUUACUUUGCGUCCCGGGAAUUCCAGCUGCGCCUGCGGGAAUAUUUGGGCUGCCGCCGGGUGCCCAGAGACACCCUGGACACGCGCCGCGAGAGCCUCUUCUCCGCCAGGACCACGUCCGUGCGCUCCGAGGCCGGUGCGCACCCUGAAGGGAUGGAGGGAGCCACCAGGCCCGGCCUCCAGAGGCAGGAGAGUGUGUUCUGAGUCCCGGGGGCGCAGCUUGGAGAGCCGGGGGCGCAGCUUGGAGAUCCAGGGGCGCAUGGAGAGGCCACGGUGCCAGAGGUUCAGGGAGAACAGCUGCGUUGCUCCCAGGCACUGCAGAGGCCCGGUGGGGAAGGGUCUCCAGGCUUUAUUCCUCCCAGGCACUGCAGAGGCACCGGUGAGGAAGGGUCUCCAGGCUUCACUCAGGGUAGAGAAACAAGCAAAGCCCAGCAGCGCACAGGGUGCUUGUUAUCCUGCAGAGGGUGCCUCUGCCUCUCUGUGUCAGGGGACAGCUUGUGUCACCACGCCCGGCUAAUUUUUGUAUUUUUUUUAGUAGAGCUGGGCUGUCACCCCCGAGCUCCUUAGACACUCCUCACACCUGUCCAUACCCGAGGGUGGAUAUUCAACCAGCCCCACCGCCUACCCGACUCGGUUUCUGGAUAUCCUCCGUGGGCGAACUGCGAGCCCCAUUCCCAGCUCUUCUCCCUGCUGACAUCGUCCCUUAGUUGUGGUUCUGGCCUUCUCCAUUCUCCUCCAGGGGUUCUGGUCUCCGUAGCCCGGUGCACGCCGAAAUUUCUGUUUAUUUCACUCAGGGGCACUGUGGUUGCUGUGGUUGGAAUUCUUCUUUCAGAGGAGCGCCUGGGGCUCCUGCAAGUCAGCUACUCUCCGUGCCCACUUCCCCCCACACACACACCCCACCCUGUUGCUGACCAAGGUGAUUUUUGGCACAUUUGUUCUGGCCUGGCUUGGUGGGACCCCACCCCUAUUCUGCUUCUGUGAGUCCCUGAUAGAGAAGGAGGUCCCAUCAGGCCCCUGGAACACACUCAGGCUUCCCUGACUCAGGACAAGGACCACGGGAGGCCCAGGUGCGGAAAGGAGGCUCCGUGAGAUGGGGUCCAGCCCAUCCCAACACAAGGGUGCAGCUUGAUUCGGGAGUUCCCCACCUCCUGCCCAUUCUCCGCGUCCUUUUACCCCAUGGAGAGCCUCAGCCAUGGCAAGUCCAUCUGGAGUCCAGGAAGCAGGCAACUGGCCUGACCCAUGAGACCGUUUGGAGACCAAGCAGCAGAUGCAGGUGUGGACCCCAGGAACCUACAGGGGUGUCAGCCGCUGAGCCCCCUCCCUGCUGUGUGGGUGGUGAGCAGGCUGGGUCUUUGUCUGUCUUCUUCUACACGGCAUGUGCCUGCACCAGCCCCAACACCUGAGCUGGUUUAGCGCAAAGAAGAGCUCUGACUCUCCAGGGGUGCUGGGACAUCACGUGGAAUUGGAUCCCAGGCUCUCUUGGGCGAGAAAGACCAUUCUGGAGGUGGGAGUGGGAGAGCUGCCUGUCUGCCCACGGGCUCUGCGUCUCCGCAGUGGGUGGCCUUGGAUGCCCGGCCCCUCCCUUUCUGUGCACUGGGGACGCUGAUGGAGGCUGAAGCUGCUGUUCGGAGGCCCUCUAUUGGUGCCUCUCUCCUGCCGUCAUCACUAUGGCAGGAAAACAGAGAUGGUUUAGUAAUGAAUUAUCAUUCCCAAACCCGUGUCCACCUGGAACAUCAGGAUGGGACCAUGUUUGAAAAUCGGGUCUUUCCAAAUGUAAUUAAGUAAGGCGAGGCCAUACUGCAUUUACAAUGGGCCCAAUCCAGUGUCCCUAUGAGAGACGGAAGAGGAGACACAGACACAAAGCAGGAGGCCACAUAAAGACAGAGGCAGAGACUGAAGUGAUGCUGCCCCAAGCCCAGGGAUGCCUGGAGUCCCCAGGAGCUGGGAGAGGCAGGAAGGACCCUCCCCUAGAGUCUCUGGAGGGAACUGGAUACAAUUGCAGAGUGCACUAAACAGUUGCCCCAGAAAGACAUGUCUUGUUUUAAAGCCCAGAACCUGAAAUUAUUAUAGAUUUUAUUCGGUAAUAAGGAACUUUGCAUGUGUAAUUACUUAAGGAUAUGAAGAUGAGAUUGUGCUGGAUUAUUAAGCACCCUAAAUGCCAUGACAGGUGUCCUUCCAAGAGACAGAAGAGGAGACACAGACACAGAGCAGGAGGACACGUGGAGACAGAGGCAGACUGGAGUGAUGCGGCCACAAGCCCAGGGACACCUGGAGCCCCCAGGAGCUGGGAGAGGCAGGAAGGAUCCUCCCCUAGAGCCUCCAGGGGGAACUGGAGGAUGCGUAAGAGACCCAGAACUUCCACAGAAGGAGGAAAAUUAACCUCCUGCUUCUCUAGACUGUUCCAAAGCUGAACCCUAGAAAGCAAAGCUGAUACAGAAGCAUCCAGGCUGCAGGAGUACAGGUCGCAAGUGCUGAGCGUGGGCCUUGGGUGUGUCUCAUGGGGGAAAAAAAACUGUGAAAAACCUCAGAGUAGCAUCUUCACAGUAACGCACGGACGAUCCCUAAACUGCCUUGUAAACAAAAAUGAGAGCUUGAGUCAGAGGAAGCCGAGACAAUAUCCUUCCUCGACAACGUGCGAGAACCCUGACGUCCCCCAGCAAAGGAAGACGUUGCAAGCAGGCAAAAUGCGUCGAUUUUUUUUUUUUGUCAGUAUGAUGAUUUUUGCAGCCACUUGGCUAUGGAGAGCAGCCGACACCCCCUCUUACAGCCGUGGAUGUUUCCUGGAAGCUGACUCAGUCUGUUCACUGGUUGAGCUUUGAGUGAAAAGAUAACACAGGUCUAUUGACUCACACACAUGUUUUAAGAUGGAAAACUUUACUUCUGUUCUUGGCAGGACAUGGAGAGAGGGAGGGAUUCCAAAAAGUCUCAGCCUCCAUCAAGGCGUGGCAGCUCAUGCCGGUAAUCUCAGCACUUUGGGAGGCUCAGGCGGGAGGACUGAUUGAGUCCGGGUGUUCAAGGGCCAACCUAGGCAACACAGUGAGAACUCAUCUCUGUAAAAAAUAAAAAUAAAACAUUAAAAAAAAACAUGAGCUUUGAAGUGCA